ACUGGACUCUGAAAUGGGCAUGUACAGAGACGAAGAGACCCCAACAUGCUUCAGGCUUUGAGUGGAGAGGACACAGCCUCUGCUGGGACAGGGAAUAGAGGGAUGUGGAGUCCCUGAAGAUGCUUUUGGACAAUGGUCUGAGGUUGGGACAGUGGCAGGAGAUACCAUUCACCCAGGAUCUCCAGGACAAGAGAUCAGCCUGGCAGUUACAUGUGUUUUUUUUCAAACUGGUUGCCAGGUUGGCAUGAACGAUGACAUCAGAGAUUCCGACCUUCCUGAUUGGAGGGACCGGACUCCGUGGUGCCUGGAGAUCAGUUGGACAACAGUAUCUUCUCAGAGCUGUUCUCUACUCCUGACUUCUCCUAGGCUUGAGAAUUGAUAACAUACUCUUCUGGAUCCUAGAAGUGUCCAGAAGAAGGCCAUGGACAGAACGGAGACUAGGUUCCGUAAGAGGGGACAGAUUACGGGAAAGAUCACGACCAGCCGUCAACCGCACCCCCAGAAUGAGCAGAGUCCCCAGCGGAGCACCUCGGGGUACCCCCUCCAGGAGGUGGUGGAUGAUGAAAUGUUGGGACCAUCAGCCCCUGGGGUAGAUCCCAGCCCCCCAUGUAGGUCCCUUGGCUGGAAAAGGAAGAGGGAGUGGUCAGAUGAAUCUGAGGAGGAGCCGGAGAAGGAGCUCGCCCCUGAGCCUGAGGAGACCUGGGUAGUGGAGAUGCUGUGUGGGCUCAAGAUGAAGCUGAAGCAACAGCGAGUGUCAUCCAUCCUCCCUGAGCACCACAAGGACUUCAACAGUCAGCUUGCCCCUGGGGUAGAUCCCAGCCCCCCGCAUAGGUCCUUUUGCUGGAAAAGGAAGAUGGAGUGGUGGGACGAAUCUGAGGAGUCGUUGGAGGAGGAGCCACGGAAGGUGCUCGCCCCUGAGCCUGAGGAGAUCUGGGUGGCGGAGAUGCUGUGUGGCCUCAAGAUGAAGCUGAAGCGACGGCGAGUGUCGCUCGUGCUCCCUGAGCACCACGAGGCCUUCAACAGGCUGCUUGAGGAUCCUGUCAUUAAAAGAUUCUUGGCCUGGGACAAAGAUCUGAGGGUGUCGGACAAGUAUCUCCUGGCUAUGGUCAUAGCGUAUUUCAGCCGGGCUGGCUUCCCCUCCUGGCAAUACCAACGCAUUCAUUUCUUCCUGGCUCUCUACCUGGCCAAUGACAUGGAGGAGGACGACGAGGACUCCAAACAAAACAUCUUCCACUUCCUGUAUAGGAAGAACCGCUCUCGCAUACCCUUGCUCCGUAAGCGUUGGUUCCAGUUAGGCCAUUCCAUGAACCCGAGGGCCAGGAAGAACCGCUCUCGCAUACCCUUGCUCCGUAAGCGUCGGUUCCAGUUAUACCGUUCCACGAACCCGAGGGCCAGGAAGAACCGCUCUCGCAUACCCUUGCUCCGUAAGCAUCGGUUCCAGUUAUACCGUUCCAUGAACUCGAGGGCCAGGAAGAACCGCUCUCAGAUAGUCCUGUUCCAGAAACGACGGUUCCACUUCUUCUGUUCCAUGAGCUGCAGGGCUUGGGUUUCCCCAGAGGAGUUGGAGGAGGUGAGUGGGGCCUGGGGAGGUGGAGGAGGUGGGGAGGAAUUGGGUGGGCUGGAGGCUGGAUGAGGGGAGAGAGGGGUAUCCUGGCGAGUCCCCGUCUUCUCAAAGGGCGUUUGUUUUUCCAGAUCCAGGCUUAUGACCCAGAGCACUGGGUGUGGGCGCGAGAUCGCGCUCACCUUUCCUAGAGCUCCAGGGACCGGGGAGGCCUGAGGUCAUCGGCCUGAGAGAAGGUACAUCUGCAUCCUCUGGGGUAAAGGCAGAAUAUUGGGGUCUAUUUCGGAAAUCCGAAGAACCCAAUUGCUUGAUCUGGCUUCAAGCCUGGGCAACGUGGCGAGAUCCCCUCUCCACAAAAAUACAAAAAUUAGCCAGGCGAUGUGGGACGCAUCUCUACUCCCAACUACUCAGGAGGCUGAGGCGGGAGGAUCGCUGGAGCCUGGAAGGUCGGGGCCGCACGGAGCCCUGAUCCUGCCACUGCACUCCAGUCUGGGCGACAGAGUGAGACCCUGCCUCAAAAAUAAUCAUAAAAACUGAGUUUGGGGAGGUUCAUUAUGAUUGACGCACUUGAGUUACUGAUUUGGGUCGAGGGUUCAGUGAAGCUUUGGUUUACAUCUUGUGCAGCUAACCACGUUGAGCACAGAGCAUGAGACUUCAUCAUGAGGAGGUAGGAUUAAGGAUUAGGCUUCUGGACUCGUGGUUCGUGAUGUUGUCACAUUAGAAACACAUCUAGCAUGGUUACAAGUUUAGAUCUUAAGUGACACAAAAGGCCCCAGCUGUGAUAAAGUCCAAAGCCACAUUCUCUGAGGGUGCCCUACUCCCUGGGCAGACCCACCCAAAGUCCUUGGUAUGAAGCAGAUCACUGGGGCUGACCUUGGGUGUAUUAAGUGAGUUUUGGAGUCGUGGUCACCAAAGUGUGAGUUUCACAGUUGAACACGAUGGUUCAGAAGCAGGGUAUAGAAUGAAAGGCAGCAGAUAAAAUUGCAUUUCUCAAUUGACAUGGGACGUGAAUAACUUUCCUGUCUAGAGAGCUGCCUCCUUGAAGUGUGACAUUGUCUCUCUCGCUUCCAGAACACCGGACCCAGGGGAGAUGUGGAUUUUCAGCAGGAACUUUAUUCCAAUGCUAAUGGCAGACACCAGGCAGGAGGAGAGGAACCAUUUGUGCAGAUCAUCUAGAAGAACCUGGACCAUUCUUGAUGGAGCUGAAUACAGUGAUCACGUUGUCCUCCUAGGAGCAGGGGUGGGGGGAGGGGGGUGGGGUCCUUCUAGGAGUCCUUGGAGAAAAGUAAGAAACCAGGAGCGUUUCCAGUUCCACCCUUUCCUGCGGCACCACCACCCUUUUUAUAUUGCUGAAUUCCAACCUCCCUGGGGCGGAACCUGGAGGUCCUGUUUCUUACGGACUUGCAGUCCAGGAGGAUUUGAAGGCACAAUGCAGGGGCUCAGAUUGGGACAGAAUUCUUUUGUGAAAUAUCAGUGCCACAGAUUGUAACAGAUAGCUUCAUGCACACUCUGCAUUUUAUUGGUUUGUUUGGAAAAUGUCGGCCAUUGAAUUAUUCAUAGAUUUAUUUCAAAUAGUUUGGAAAUUGUUGUACUUUUGAAAACAUGCUGUUCCUGUAGUUUUUUGAUGAGAGUUAUAGUUGUUAUAUAUACAUAAAGCUAAUUUUCUUUUCAUUUUUAAGAGACAAUUCUUUUAUCCUAAAUAUUUUAUUAUCUUUAAAUUUGUUUCUGUAUUAUUAUAUGUGCUCCUGAAGCGAGCACUCUUUUUAUCUAUGAUACUUCCAUAAUAAUCUCUUCUAUUUAUAGCUAUUGGUAGUUCCCCACCA